GUCGCCUCGGGCAGGGUAGCCAGCGGCUGCAUCUGAGGCGGACGCCGCAGUGUAGGGCACACCCUGAGGGUAGCGAGAGACGUGACAGGACCGAGCAGCUGGGGGCUGCAGCCUGCUCUGUCCCCACCGAUCCCAGAGAGAGGCUGUGAGUCUGGAUCUGGGCGUUCGCACCCUGAGAGAGGGGGUCAAAGCUCCCCUGCGGCCCCGAGGAAGAAGAGCAAGGUUGAGGACAGCCUCGGGUCACCAGAGUAGUUUGGAGGCAGGCCUGCAGGCGCGUCCCCGCUCCUCAGCUCCAAGCUGACGUAUCUACACCUGCCGGCGGGCAUUAAGAUGGCUGGUUAUGCCACUACUCCCAGCCCCAUGCAGACCCUUCAGGAGGAAGCGGUGUGUGCCAUCUGCUUGGAUUACUUCAAGGACCCCGUGUCCAUCAGCUGUGGGCACAACUUCUGCCGAGGGUGUGUGACCCAGCUGUGGAGUAAGGAGGACGAGGAGGACCAGAACGAGGAGGAAGAUGAAUGGGAGGAGGAGGAGGACGAGGAAGCGGUGGGGGCCAUGGAUGGAUGGGACGGCUCCAUUCGAGAGGUGUUGUAUCGGGGGAAUGCUGACGAAGAGUUGUUCCAAGACCAAGAUGACGAUGAACUCUGGCUCGGUGACAGUGGUAUAACUAAUUGGGACAACGUAGACUAUAUGUGGGACGAGGAGGAAGAAGAAGAAGAGGAAGAUCAGGACUAUUACCUAGGAGGCUUGAGACCUGACCUGAGAAUUGAUGUCUACCGAGAAGAAGAAAUACUGGAAGCAUACGAUGAGGACGAAGAUGAAGAGCUGUAUCCUGACAUCCACCCGCCUCCUUCCUUGCCCCUUCCAGGGCAGUUCACCUGCCCCCAGUGCCGAAAGAGCUUUACACGUCGCAGCUUUCGUCCCAACUUGCAGCUGGCCAACAUGGUCCAGAUAAUUCGCCAGAUGUGCCCCACUCCUUAUCGGGGAAACCGGAGUAAUGAUCAGGGCAUGUGCUUUAAACACCAGGAAGCCCUGAAACUCUUCUGUGAGGUGGACAAAGAGGCCAUCUGUGUGGUGUGCCGAGAAUCCAGGAGCCACAAACAGCACAGCGUGCUGCCUUUGGAGGAGGUGGUGCAGGAGUACCAGAGUCUCGCUCUGUUGCCCAGGCUGGAGUGUGGUGGCACGAUCUCGGCUCACUGCCAGCUCCGCCUCCUGGAUUCAUGCCAUUCUCCUGCCUCAGCCUGCCGAGUAGCUGGGACUACAGGCGCCCGCCACCAAGCCUGGCUAAUUUUUUGUAUUUUUAGUAGAGACAGGGUUUCACCGUGUUAGUCAGGAUGGUCUCGAUCUCCUGACCCCGUGAUCUGCCCGCCUCGGCCUCCCAAAGUGCUGGGAUUACAGGCGUGAGCCACCGCGCCCGGCCUCUUUCUUUCUUUCAAUGCUUUUGUUUUUGUUUUGUUUGAGCCAGGGUCUCACUCUGUUGCCCAGACUGGAGUGCAGUAGUGCAAUCACAGCUCACUCACUUCCUACGUUCAAGUGAUGCUCCCACGUCAGCCUUCUGUGUAACAAGGACUAUAGUGCAGCUAAUUUAUUUUUAUUUUUUGUGGAGAUCUCCCUACAUUGCCCAGGCUGGUCUUGAACUCCUGGUGGGCUCAAGUGAUCCUCCUGCCUUGGCCUCCCAAAAUGCUGGGAUUACAGUCAUGAGCCACCACACCCAGCCUAGACCAGGAUUUCUCAACCUCGACCCUAUUGACAUUUUGAGUGAGAUAAUUCUUUGUUGUGGGCAGCUGUCCUAUGCAUUAUAGGAUACUUAGUAGCAUCUCUGGACUCUACCCACUACAUGCAGGUAGUACCCCUCCACUAGUUGUGACAACCACAAAUGUCUCUAGACAUUACCAAAUGUCCCAUAAGCAGACAUUGCAAAAUCAUCCCCAGUUGAGAACCACUGAUGUAGUCAGGGAAAGUGGUCAUGUCCACAUAUCAUCCUCUUGUAGGCACUAUAGCCGGUGCCUGGCAUAGGUGUUCAAAAGUGGAACACCUACUCUUGAGAGGAAGAAUAGGCUUGCCUAGCUAGCACUUUAUUAAAAGUACCCUGAGGGCCAGGCACGGUGGCUCAUGCCUGUAAUCCCAGCACUUUGGGAGGCCGAGGUAGGCAGAUCACCUGAGGUCGGGAGUUCCAGACCAGCCUGACCAACAUGGAGAAACCCUGUCUCUGCUAAAAAUACAAAAUUAGCCAGGCAUGGUGGCGCAUGCCUGUCAUCCCAGCUACUCAGGAGGCUGAGGCAGGAGAAUCACUUGAACCUGGGAGGAGGAGGUUGCAGUGAGCCGAGAUCGCACCAUUGCACUCCAGCCUGGGCAACAAGAAUGAAACUCCAUCUCAAAAAAAAAAAAAAAAAGUACCCUGAGUAUCAGUGGAUUAGUGGAUAUGACACCCACUACUCCCUGCUCUUGGAGUGGGGUAGCAAAGUCAACAAACCUUUUCUAAACAUUACCGCUGCUUAUGUCACUUGGAUUUGGGAGAACAAGAACCGUGACAGAUAAACAGUUUACAAAAUCAAGCUCUGGAGAUUUUGAGUAAUAACAAUCACUUCAGCUACUCAGUUCCAGCAGAGCAGUAGGGAUGUCAUUUUUUGUUUUCAGGUAUUACGCAGAACCACUGAGUCCACAGUGGAGGUGGCCCUGGUAAUAUAACAUCAGUCCCUAAAGUACUUUCUUAAAACCUAAGGCUCUUGCCAUUGACCAUCAACCCCUGGCCUCUAUGCCAUGCCUCCUGAAACUCCUAUAAGACUUGUAGAUUCUAUGCUGCUUCCUACCCCCAAUUCCUAACUCCUCUGAAAAUUAUCCUGUAACAGUGAAGUUAUUGCAAAUAUUUGCUGGCUGGUAAAAUGGGGUUAUAAGAAAGGAAGCUAAAGACGCUAGUCCUCCACAUUCAAGCUAAUAGAACUUCAUGUAACAAUGGAAGUAUUCUGUAUCUGCUGUCUAAUACAGUAGAUACUACUAGCUACAUAUGACUUGAGCUCUUGAAAUGUGGCUAGUGCACCUCAUGAACUCAAUUUUUAAGAUAGUAUUUAAUUUAAUUUUAAUUAGCCACAUGUAGCUAGUGGCUAUCAAAUCCUAUUUAACAGCACAGUUCUGUACAACCAAAGUCUAGUUCUUCCUGGGGCCCUUGGGAGUAGCAAGUCCAAGGGGGAGGAUAAAAACAGAAAUGAAACAAUUUUCUUUUUCCAGCUGGGAGCGGUAGGCUGUAAGGUAAUAUUUUUAGACAUAAAAGGAGAAAAUAUUUUAUUUUUAAAAUCUGACCAAAAUGAUCUUGAGCCACCUAUCACUUCUGAUACACGUGGAUCACACGGGUGACGAGACAGGAGAAAACUAGGGGAAACAAGUUAGAAAAUAAACUGUAUUACCUUCUCCUAUCAAAAAAGGUCUGGGGCUAGAGCUGGAGCCUCAAAAUAGGAGGGAUAAUAAAUAUAGGGUUUUACUUUGUGCCUGACUUUUUGAAAAUGGGAUGGGGGGCAAAACCUAGUAUUGAAGCAGGUAAGUGGGUUCUUUCCGUGUUACAGCAGAUGAGGGUGAUGAGGAGCUCUUGGAGUCCUGGAAGAGAGAGCAGCCUGUGCUGACAGAGUUAAUGAGAGGACAGAUCUAGGAGUAACAGGGUCUGAGGAGAGGAGAUGGCCUCCCAGACCAUGAGAACUAACAGUUGUGAUAAAUUUAAUCAUAGUCUGUCCAAACCAGAGAGUCCUCAAGUGUGGUAUGAGAAUCCUGGGUGUGGGGCAGUGAGCUCAUUUCUGCUCUUGAGAAGUGUAGGAGAUGCAGCAAGGUUCCUGCUAUCAGGAGACCUGCAAAGAUGGAAGGAAACGUUCCUCUAAGUUAUUACUUGUCUCACCUCCUCCCUCCCCCAAAGGAAGGGGAAAGAUAGACACCUCGGGGAUUUGAAUUAGAAAUAGCCCUUUGGAGGGUUUUUUUGUUUGUUUGUUGUUGUUAUUGUUGUUUUCCAUUUUUUUUACACAGCUCCAAACAGCCAACUGAAAUAAAAAUAGCCUUUAAGAACAAGGAGGCUUAUCCUCUAUAGCGAUUCCCCCUGCUGAGGUUUGUGCUUAGGCCUUCCUAGCUUUCUCGUCUCAUCUUUUUUCUUUUUUUUUUUGAGUUUUGCCCUUGUCGCCCAGGCUCUGGAGUGCAGUGACACGACCUCGGCUCACUGCAACCUCCACCUCCCAGGUUCAAGCAGUUCUCCUGCCUCAGCCUCCAGGGUAGCUGGGAUUACAAGCAUGUGCUACCACGCCCAGCUAAUUUUUUUAUAUUUAAAAAAAUUAAAAUGUAAUUUUAAUUGUUGGCCAGGCUGGUCUCGAACUCCUGACCUCAGGUGAUCUGUCCACCUCGGCCUCCCAAAGUGCUGGGAUUAUAGGCAGGAGCCACCACGCCCAGCCAUCUCCCCUCAUCUUAAGGGACCGAGAUCCCAACUUAGAGCCCUUUGGUUGACAAUUCCAGCUGGCAGUAAGCAGAGUCCUACAAAGAUAAGGAGGGAUCCAGGUGGCCUGGAGAGGAUCCAUGGAGCUCACAUCCCCUUUUUCUCUGACAUUUCUUAGGCACAUGGAAUCCCUUCUACUCCUACAGCAAAGGAUGUGAUUUCUCCGCAGGCCCUGGCCAUUUAGCCUUAGUGUGAGCAGAGAGGACUGCCCUUCAUCCCUCAUACAAAUUUGAGCUAGCCAGCCCCAGGGUUCCAUUCUGACCUUUUUCGCACUCUGGUUUAUAUGACGUCCUCUCUCCAGUAGAAAGCUGAGAAAAUGAAACUUGGGUCAUCUUUUGUUUCUCUCUACCAUCUAAUGCUACUUUAAAUCCUUUGACAAGGAGGCUAGAAGCUUGACUUCUCCCUGCAUUUCUUUUUUUUUUUCUUUUUUUGAGAUGCAGUCUCCCUCUGUUGCCCAGGCUGGAGUGCGGUGACGCAAUCUCGGCUCACUGCAACCUCUGCCUCCUGGGUUCAAGUGAUUCUCCUGCCUCAGCCUCCCAAGUAGCUGGGAUUACAAGCAUGCACCACCACGCCCAGCUAAUUUUUGUAUUUUUAGGAGAGACAGGGUUUUGCCAUGCUGGUCAGGCUGGUCUUGAACUCCUGACCUCAAGUGACCCACCUGCCUUGGCCUCCCAAAGUGCUGGAAUUACAGGCAUGAACCACCGCGCCCGGCCAUCCCUGCAUUUAUUAUAGUCCUGUCUGGACCAUCCCCUUUCCACAGCCUCUGACUCUGUAUCUGCCAAAGCACCCAGGCCUAGCCCACAGUCCAUCUCCCAAGGAAGCCCCAACAGACAACAGAAUGCUUUCUGGGGGACUGCUAGACGUCAGACUUCUGCCUAAAAUUUAUGCUGAAUCUUUAUCAGGAAAAUAAACAUUUUUUUAAAAAGUUAAUGACCAGGCUGGCCAACAUGGUGACACCCUGUCUCUACCAAAAAAGACAAAAAUUAGCCAGGCAUGUAGUCCCAGCUACUCGGGAGACUGAGGUGGGAGAAUUGUCUGAACCCAGGAGGCGAAGGGUGCUGUGAGCCAAAAUGGCACCACUGCACUCCAGCCUGGGUGACAGAGUGAGACGCUGUCUCAAAAAAAAAAAAAAAAAAAAACUGCAAGUGAUCUCUGAUCUCUUUGUAAGAUUUGUUCCAGGAACUGAUUUAAUUUCACAGCCGACCUCACUAAGAGUGGGACAGCACCUAUACUUGUACUCCUGUUUCCUGGUCUCCAAACUUUUUGUGCUUAAUUUUUUUUUUUUCUUUUUGAGACAGGAUCUUACCCUGUCACCCAGGCUGGAGUGUAGUGAUGUGAUCAUAGCUCACUGCGGCCUCCAACUUCUGGGCUCAAGCGAUCCUCCUGCAUCAGCCUCCUAAGUAGCUGGGACUACAAGCGUGCACCACCAUGCCUGGCUAAAAUUUUUAAAAAUUUUAUAGCGAUGGGGUCUCACUGUGUUGGUCUUGAACACCUGAGUUCAAGUGAUCCUCCCACCUCAGCCUCCCAAACUGCUGGGAUUACAGGUGUGAACCAUGCUCAACCAAAGAGCUCCUAUAUACAGAGGCCAAUUCUAGACACUGGAGUGAAGGAAGUAGUGUAGGGAUGAGAGAGACCUCUUAGUCAUAAGGUCUUUAGUAAGUACUCAGUCCCUCCUUUAGUGCCACUUCGUAGGAAUCUUGCACCACCACCCCCAGCUAAAUUUAGGGUCCCCCUAGAGACCUUCCUGUACAGCAUCUCAGCCUUUGGCUUGACUCAUUUGUCUUGAAUACUGCAGUGGCUUCUUAACUCUUCUUGUCUCUAGUUUUACUCCUCCAACCUAGCCUGCACCGUGACAAUAAGUGCGUUUUUAGCAGGUAGCAAUAAAAACUUGUCCUAAAAAAAGAA